GCCCUGCCCGCGCCACCCAGGGAGGGCGCGCCCUUCCCAGCUCUGUGCUCUUCAGAACCUUGGCUUUUGUGUUACCACACGCUUUUAGCUCAAGCCCGACAAAAGCAGGAACCAGGACCAGGGGCAGAGACGAUCUUGAAGAUAAGUCAGAAAAGUCAUUUCACGCUAAAGGUCCUGUGGGUGGUGUCAGAGCAGAUGAGGCCUCGCUUAGGAGAGCGAAACACAGGAGAGACCCCACAUUCCUCCCACGGAGCAGCAAGGCCAGUAGCCGCUGUGACAGUGCUCACUGCUGGCAGUUUCCAAAUCUCCAGAGGAGUUCCUUAGAUCCUUCAAAGGGGAACCUUCCAGUGUGUUCUUCACACCUGAUGUGCGUCCUCACACCUGAUGAGUCUGUGCUUUGGUGUUAGAGGACUCACACCUGGGGCUGGACCUGAGUGUUUUUCUAAGUGUGGCUACCGCUGACGGGCAGGUGCCAUCCAUCAGGCUGAGGCUCGGCUCUUAUGCUAACCUGAGGCCCCAUGGCUGGCGGCCCUGCUGGUGUGGACGACCGCUGUGUGCGUCUCUUGAUGGCUGGGGAGCAUUUUGUUUAAACAGGAUCUUUAAAAUGAAGUGUACGCUUAUAAUACAAGUGAUGCUUGUGUAUUUCUCACUUUAGGAAAUAAAAUAUUUGCCAAUUUGAUAGAAUUUUGACUUUAACGUUAAUCGUAUUUUUAGAUAUUGGUUAGCAUAUUUUAUGUUAGGUUAUUUUCAUUUGAUUUUAUCUAGUUGUACGUAGAAGAUACUGUCAUCUUUUAGGACAAAGUAUUGUAAAAUUAUCUGUUUUAGCCCAUGUUCUGAUGACCCACAGCUCUGUCACCUUUGAGCAUCAUCUCCCCAUUCUAAGUUUUUUUCCCACUUAAUUCCUAACCCUGCCUCUUUGAGGAAGCCCAUUGACGGGGCAAUUAAAACCUUCUCAUUGCUCCUGAGACCAGAACGGCAAGAUGUUUCCUUUCAGAAGCUGAGAGCCACAAGGAGGACAGCAGUGAGCAUCUGCACAGAAACGAGCUCAGAGACGCCCGUGUUCAGUGGAGCACGCCGAUGGGGUGGGCGCCCUGGCUCUAGACGCUCUCCUAACACACCUGUGCUUUGAUGACAGUCUGCAGGAGCUGCCUGGUGAAGUACCUGGAGGAGAACAACACCUGCCCCACCUGCAGGAUUGUGAUCCACCAGAGCCACCCCCUGCAGUACAUCGGUCAUGACAGAACCAUGCAAGAUAUUGUUUACAAAUUGGUACCAGGCCUCCAAGAAGCGGAAAUGAGAAAGCAGAGGGAGUUCUAUCACAAAUUGGGCAUGGAGGUGCCGGGAGACAUCAAGGGGGAGACCUGCUCUGCAAAACAGCACUUAGAUUCCCAUCGGAAUGGUGAAACCAAAGCAGACGACAGUUCAAACAAAGAGGCCGCGGAGGAGAAGCCGGAGGAGGACAACGACUACCACCGCAGCGACGAGCAGGUGAGCAUCUGCCUGGAGUGUAACAGCAGCAAACUGCGCGGGCUGAAGCGGAAGUGGAUCCGCUGCUCAGCCCAGGCGACCGUCUUGCAUCUGAAGAAGUUCAUCGCCAAAAAACUCAACCUUUCAUCCUUUAACGAGCUGGACAUUUUAUGCAACGAGGAGAUCCUGGGCAAGGACCACACACUCAAGUUCGUGGUUGUCACUAGGUGGAGAUUCAAGAAGGCGCCGCUCCUGCUGCACUACAGACCCAAGAUGGACUUGCUGUGAAUGGUGCCACACAGCGCCCACAGACUGGGCCCUCGCACCCUUGGGUGCUCCCGGCCGCCGCGCUUAAGAACAUUGCCUCUGGGUGUCAUGUGGACCAGACUUCUGAAUAGAGAAUAUUUAUAACUUUUGUAUGAGAGAGAAUUCACACUCAACAAGACACUACCAGCACCACGUUUACAGAGGAUGAAAACACUUCACAGUCUCCCAGAGCCGAUCGUCCUCUCCCCCGCCCCACCCCGUGCUUCAGCCUUGCAGGGAGAGUGAUGCUCCAGGCAACACGGUUCUGAGUCACCUUCUGACACGAGCUCCCUCUGCUUGCUUUCCAGGUCUUGAAAAUCUGAAUUCACUUCAGUUUAGUUUAUGAAUUUUAGGUUUCAUGAUAAGCCUCAAGUGUAGUUGGACUUUUAUUGAAUCCUUCCUAAGUUAUUGAAAAAAUGUCUUUUCAUGGUGAAUGACAAUAUUUAUGUUGCCUUUAGCUUCUUGAAGAUUUAGAAGUUAUAUAAAAAAUUAAUUUAAAAGCAAACCAAAAGAGGUUUCCAUUAACAUUAUGAUUUAACCAUUGUAUUUAAUUUCCCACCUUAUGAAACACAACAGCAGCUCCCUGACUGGUUCGCCUUUCAUUGUGUGAGGUCGGCACUUGGACUCACUCAGAACUGUCGCUCACCUGUGGCUGACACACCCAGCCCUGGAAACGGGGCCCCAGACGCCACGUCGGGAUUUCUGACAUGCUCAGCAGGUAGACCAGAGGCCGUGUGACCAGCUCAGUGCUGGUUUACGGAACAACUCUUACUUUUAAAAAUUACUUGUUCCCCCAAAUUGUUGAGUGCCGCCGUUUGGUUUCCUAUGUUUUCUUUCCCUGUUUUGAUUUUGCUGAAGGGAGAGGUGGUGGUGGUUAGGAUCAGAGCUCUCCUGGCAUCCGUGGGGAGGAUUUGCUGGUGGUGGCUUCGGGCUCAUGCCCAGACACACUCACUGCCCCGUCUGUCCAAGGCCUCCCCUUCCCCUUUGCUGGUGGGAGGAGCUCGUGUGCUCCUUGGCCGCUUACUGGAAGGGCGUUUUUCAGAGCUGCAGGGACAGGGUGAGCAGCUGAAGGGCUAGGAGGGAAGCCGGCCCCCGCUCUGCAGAAGCUGCAUUUCAGCUGAAUCUGUGUUUCAGCCUCAGUUGGUUGCACCGUUAGCCCCUCUCCUCCCGGAUGGUCAUGUUUUUGUCACAUUAGAGAAUAAACAGCCACACACACAUUUUUUUUUUUCCUUUAAAACAGUAACUUGGAAAUAUGAAAAGGCCAGAAGGAGGAGCAAGGGCUGUUUUCUGGAGUGGUUGAGGUGUUGUCCUGCAGUUGUCAUUGUCUUCUCCACCGGGCUGUUCCCAUUUAUUUCCUGUGGAACUGAAUCCCUCCUCCCUCCACUCCUUGGGAGCCCAGGUGGUCCUUGGCCACCAUUCAGGCUUUCCAAGAAGCCAACCACCUUGGAGAUUUUUUUUCUUGAAUUUCGCUGUUUUCUUCUGCUUCCUUUAGAUAAAAAGCAGCUCAAGAGACCUUAUCUUAGGGAUGAGAAAAACAUGCAUAUUAAUUCCAUCUGAGUGAUUGUCAGUGUAAGGCCUUUUAAAACAAAAGCAAGUUCUUUGUUAGGAAUUGGUCAAAAUUCAUCUCUUUCUUUAAGCCCAUCAACUCCCAGGACGGUUUGAGUUACUCAGUUACCUAAGCUUGCUAUUCAUCCAAAUCAUUUUCUAGAGUCACUGUAUAAGGGUCUAUGAGUAGCUGUGUAUGAAUAAAUAUUACCUGUCUACCUCAAAAUACACAUACUGCUGAAGCAUUCUGUACAACCGUGUGUUAUCACAGUGCAGUUUUAAGUGUAACGUUAGAACUUAGGCAUUUUCCUGUGUGGCGGAAUAAGAAAGGAUUAAACAGUUACAAGCCUCCAAAUUCAAAUAAAAUUAAAUCACAGUUCAGAUGAAACUGAAUAUCAUUGUAAUAAUCUCAUAAUAUAUAUUUGUAACUUUGUAGCUAUCUUUGAAAUCACUUGACUUUGCAAUGGUGCUAAGCUGAUAGAUUUAAAUACACAGACGGGCGAGUGGCGCCCGUGUCGAUGUCUUCAGCCAGUGGUGACCCUGCUUUUGUAACCGCGUUAACCUGACAAAACCUCAGCAGCAGAAGUCCCUAUUUUUCUAGGAGUUCAUCGUGCAGACAGUCUUCACUACAGGACUCGGCCCUGGGGCCUCUGCCUCUCGUCUGACCUUGCAGCCUUAGUCGUUGGAGGCUGGAGCGCAAUGGCCCUGCCGUCUGUGGAGCCUCUGGGCGGCCUUCUUUCCUUUCUGUCAACCUCUCAUUUCACAGAAAAAGGCUGAAUUUCAUUUUUUCCAGCAUGAAAGCCAGGAUCGGUUAGUGGUUGGAUUCUAUUGGUUUUUUUUUUUUAAACAGAUGGAGUUACUGUGAAGAAGUUUUCACAACUAUUUAUGCUGGUAAAACAAAUGCUGUUAAAUCACCUUAUGCGUCGUUUUCAACAGCAGUGGGGCUAAUUACCCGGAAUACGGUCUCACCGAUGCAGUUUUCAUGGACAUAGAAAAUUCAAAUAGAAUAUAUAAUAUUGAAUUUAAGAUUUGGGGGGUUAAAAAAGAAAACUUAACUUUAUAAAAUUAUUUAUUCUAUUUUAAGCCUUCUAUCAUAUUUUCCCAUCCAAUUGUUUGGUUUCAGUGGUCCAGCUUUAUUUACAGGCAUAUAAAAUGAAAUUGUGAGAUGUUUUGCAAGCUUCUUUUUACUUUGAGUAGCUUUUAAUUUGUAUGUUUUUAUGUGGAUGAAGAGCAUUUUUUAUGCUUUUGUGCAAUAGGUUCCAAUAUGCAUUUAUUAGACAUCUGUUUAAAUGGUAAUGUAGCAUUUAUUUUGCUAAAUUGAAAGGGAACAUAGAUGGAAUUCCAAAAUAUGUACAUUCAGCUGUUUGGUUUUUCGUUUUUCAUUGUUAUUAUUGUGAGAAUGCUGUUAUUGGGGUUGUGUGUGAGUGCCCGUCAGCCAGUGAUGCCUCGGGCCACGCUGUGGGGCCACCUCAGUCCUGCCUGGGUCCUGGUGCCUUGGACCCCACGUGCUUGUGGCCAGGCUGCCCCUGGGCAGGGCCAUGUGGCCUCAGACCACAAGAGCGGAGCUGCCCUGGCCCAAGCACUGCAGCUGCCUGCACCCCCGGGCUUCGCAGCCUUGCUUGUUUUCUCUGAACAGCAACAGAACAGUGUUCACAGCGAUUCAAAGGGUGGCAUUGGGUUGGACGUUCUGGGUACAAGCCAACCUAGUCCCACGUUGUACGUGAAUGUUUAAUGUGCUCUCAAAACAUGGAAAAUAAGUUUAGUGCACAUAGCUAAAUCACAAAACAUCCAAUUUCUCUGUUUCCUCAGGAAGUCAUUACUGCGCCACCACAUCACAUGACCUUAACAUGAUCAAUGUAUUUCUCUGCCUUGACAUUUAAAUACAUAAAUUGAGAUAAGUAGAUUAGAAAAUCAUUCAAAUGAUACCAUAAUUUGUACGGGACAGGGUGCGGGCAAUGGCCACGUGGCCAAGGCCCUGCAGGAACGCGCCGAGGUCUCCCUCACCCUCCAGGUGUCCUUCGCACCCAACAGUGCGUCUGAGGAACGAGCUGCAGUUUGAGCGUUCCCCUGAGAUGUGCGUAGCCUCCGUGUAAAUGUCCACUCCCAUGGCUUAAUUGCCUAUCAGACGCAUUUUCCCAGACGAAAGCAAUGUUGGGUUGGGGAAGACAGUGCAGCCACCCAGCCUUUACCAGCAGCGUACGGCAGACGAAGGCAGUCGAGGUGUGGAGGUGAUCACGAAGAUACAUGUGUUUGACUGUUUAAUUUGAAAGUUUACAUUUUUUAUGCUUUGUGUUGGUGUGUAAUUUUUGUACUCUUGGUGGCUAGUUUUUGUCAAAUCUUUUUUGGAAUAUUGCUUAAAUGUUUUGAUUUUAUGAUAGUGAAGCUUGUAUUCAGUGUUUUGCCAAUUAAUAUUAUAUGCUUGUAAUAAAAGCAAAAGAAAAGCUUAA